AGCUUCCCCAAGGUGCAGGCGCGGUGAAACCAUCGAGACGGAGGGCCAGAGAGUCACGGCGGUGAGAGGGCUGAGUGACGGGUUACCCCAAACCAUGUGGCUGGAGGCGCGAGCUGGGGUGUGGGCGAGGUUCAGGAGGGGGUUCCUGGGUGUCGCGGAGGGGCCGGGGACGGGAGAGCUUUGUCUGUGGCCUUCCAUGCAUAGGUGUUUUGGAAUUCUGGAUCCCAGUUCUGAGGCUCAGCCGAGGUCACUGCUGUCAGCUCACCUCCCUGCAUGCCAGGCGCAGGGCAAAGUGGCCGGGGUUCGGGGUUGGAGGAGAGGUGUACUAGAAACAACUUUGCUCUUGUCCCUCAGGAUCUUAUUGUCUACGAUGUGACGAUCCGUGGAGAAAGUAGCAGAUGGGCAGAUUUUCAUUUGGGGAGAAUGAGGGAGAAAAGAACGGGCAUUCCGAGCCAAGAGCACUGCAUGAGCAAGGAGUUGGGAGGUUGCUUACUUGUUGAACAUAUUUGUUGCGUAUUUGCAUAUUUGCUAAACAGGUAGUGUUAGGAGCUAAUCCAUGAAAGGUAGGUGGGCGCCGUAUUGUAGAGAGCCUUGAGUACCAGGCUGAGUUUAUACCCAAUUCAGGGGUCUGCUGGGAGCCAGCCAUUGAAGGUGCUGGAGCAGAGAGAGAUAUGGUAUUGGAGCUGAUCCCUAUGAUGAAAGAUCUGGACCCUUGUGUAGAUGUUCCGUGAAGCAGGAGGUGAAGACCUAUUAAAAUGCCAUUUCAAGAACUACGAUUUUAAAGACAGUUUAGGUGGGAGGUAAUAAAGGUCUAAACAAGACGUUAAAUAUUGGGGACGUAAGGGGGAGGAUAUUUGAAGGACAUUACUCAUAACAAGACAUAGGGUUACUGACAAGUCAACGGACGCUUCUCCCUUGCUGACUGCAGCCAAUGGACCCCUUUUUAUCAUAGCUGGUCCCAGGGACCACAAAAAUCCUGUCCAUCCAUUACCCUGAUGUGAAGCCUGUUUAUAUAGCUCUUUUUGGUUUAAGGCAUCUCCAGACAUGGUCCUCUGGUAGGAAACAGGUAUGAGUAGACUAAUGAAGGACAAAAUGGGAUGAGGGACCUGGAGCCUCCACCCUUGCAUUCCAAUACCACCCUUACCCCACAAAAGGAGGGUAUUGACCCACACAGUAAUGCUGACCUGUGGCCAGGGCUGGGGAGGUCCAAUUUCUAAUCUGUGCUUUGUCCCAUCUCCACUGUUCCCCACCCCUAGGUUUUCGUAACACCCCAGGGCCUGUAAGGUUUGGUGUUUCCCUUUCAAGAUGCCACUUUCAGACUUUAUUCUGGCUCUGAAGGACAAUCCCUACUUUGGGGCUGGAUUUGGGCUGGUGGGUGUGGGCACAGCCCUGGCCCUGGCCCGGAAGGGUGUCCAACUGGGCCUGGUGGCAUUCCGGCGCCAUUACAUGAUCACACUGGAAGUCCCUGCUCGAGACAGGAGCUAUGCCUGGUUGCUUAGCUGGCUCACCCGCCACAGUACCCGUACUCAGCACCUCAGUGUCGAGACUUCGUACCUUCAGCAUGAGAGUGGCCGCAUUUCCACUAAGUUUGAAUUUGUCCCCAGCCCUGGAAACCAUUUUAUCUGGUAUCGGGGGAAAUGGAUUCGGGUAGAACGAAGUCGAGAGAUGCAGAUGAUAGACUUGCAGACGGGGACUCCUUGGGAAUCUGUCACCUUCACGGCCCUGGGCACUGACCGAAAGGUUUUCUUCAACAUCCUGGAGGAAGCUCGAGAGCUAGCCUUGCAGCAGGAGGAAGGGAAGACCGUGAUGUACACAGCUGUGGGCUCUGAAUGGCGUCCCUUUGGCUAUCCACGCCGCCGGCGACCACUGAAUUCUGUGGUUCUACAACAGGGUCUGGCUGACCGAAUUGUCAGAGACGUCCAGGAAUUCAUCGAUAACCCCAAGUGGUACACUGACAGAGGCAUUCCUUACAGACGUGGCUACCUGCUUUAUGGGCCCCCUGGUUGCGGAAAGAGCAGUUUUAUCACAGCCCUGGCUGGGGAACUGGAGCACAGCAUCUGCCUGCUGAGCCUCACGGACUCCAGCCUCUCUGAUGACCGACUCAACCACCUGCUGAGCGUGGCCCCGCAGCAGAGCCUGGUACUCCUGGAGGAUGUGGAUGCUGCUUUUCUCAGUCGAGACUUGGCUGUGGAGAACCCAGUAAAGUACCAAGGCCUAGGUCGCCUCACCUUCAGUGGACUGCUCAAUGCCUUGGAUGGUGUGGCUUCCACCGAGGCCCGCAUCGUGUUCAUGACCACCAACCACGUUGACAGGCUGGACCCUGCCCUGAUACGCCCGGGGCGAGUGGACCUGAAGGAGUACGUGGGCUACUGCUCACACUGGCAGCUGACCCAGAUGUUCCAGAGGUUCUAUCCAGGGCAGGCACCUUCCUUAGCUGAGAACUUUGCAGAACAUGUCCUUCGAGCUACAAACCAGAUCAGUCCUGCCCAGGUGCAGGGCUACUUCAUGCUGUAUAAAAAUGACCCUGUAGGGGCAAUUCACAAUGCUGAGUCUCUGAGGAGGUGAUCAGGCUGGGCUCAGCUCAGCUCUCCUCCUCUAGCUCAAUAAACAUCUGCCACACUA